AGUGAGACCGCGCGGCAACAGCUUGCGGCUGCGGGGAGCUCCCGUGGGCGCUCCGCUGGCUGUGCAGGCGGCCAUGGAUUCCUUGCGGAAAAUGCUGAUCUCAGUCGCAAUGCUGGGCGCAGGGGCUGGCGUGGGCUACGCGCUCCUCGUUAUCGUGACCCCGGGAGAGCGGCGGAAGCAGGAAAUGCUAAAGGAGAUGCCACUGCAGGACCCAAGGAGCAGGGAGGAGGCGGCCAGGACCCAGCAGCUAUUGCUGGCCACUCUGCAGGAGGCAGCGACCACGCAGGAGAACGUGGCCUGGAGGAAGAACUGGAUGGUUGGCGGCGAAGGCGGCGCCGGCGGGAGGUCACCGUGAGACCGGACUUGCCUCCGUGGGCGCCGGACCUUGGCUUGGGCGCAGGAAUCCGAGGCAGCCUUUCUCCUUCGUGGGCCCAGCGGAGAGUCCGGACCGAGAUACCAUGCCAGGACUCUCCGGGGUCCUGUGAGCUGCCGUCGGGUGAGCACGUUUCCCCCAAACCCUGGACUGACUGCUUUAAGGUCCGCAAGGCGGGCCAGGGCCGAGACGCGAGUCGGAUGUGGUGAACUGAAAGAACCAAUAAAAUCAUGUUCCUCCACCCAGAAUGAGCCCUGCAGUCGACACCUACCAAUGCUUAGAGACGCGUGGUCGGUGCUGGGGGCGCGGCCUGGAGCUGCUGCCUGUCCCACCCCACCAGAAGAGGCUGAUCCCGAUAGGUAUCUGACCACAUUUUUUUUUUUUUUUUUUUUUUGAGACGGAGUCAAUGUCACCCAGGCUGGAGUGCAGUGGCACGAUCUCGGCUCACUGCAACCUCCGCCCCUGGGUUCCAGCAAUUCUCCUGCCUCAGCUUCCCGAGUAGCCGGGAUCACAAGUGCGCGCCACCAAGCCCAGCUAACUUUUGUGUUUUUAGUUGAGACAGGGUUCACCAUGUUGGCUAGACUGGUCUCGAACUCCAGACCCAGGUGAUCCGCCCGCCUCGGCCUCCCAAAGGGCUGGGAUUACAGGCGUGAACCACCUCGCCCUGCCGCGGCCACAUUUUUUCUUUUUUUUGAGAUGGAGUCUUGCUCUUGUCACCCAGGCAGGAGUGCAGUGGCGCAAUCUUGGCUCACUGCAACCUCUGCCUCCUGGGUUCAAGCUGUUCUCCUUACUCAGCCUCCCAUGUAGCUGGGAUUACAGGCGUCCGCAACCACGCCCGGCUGAUAUUAGUAGUUUUAGUAGAGGCGGGUUUCACCAUGUGGCCAGGCUGAUCUCGAACUCCUGACCUCAGGCAGUUCACCCGUCUCAGCCUCCCAAAGUGCUGGGAUUAGAGGCGUGAGCCACUGCGCCCGGCCAACCACAUUUUCAAAACAGGUCAUGUGGUGUCAGGUUGGAGUGUACUUCCAGGGAUAACCGUGGGACAUUCUUGAAAUCUGAACUAUCCUGGGAAGUCUUGAAGUAAUGGAUGCCUAUAGUGGACACUCAGGACUCCUGUCCUUGGAGCGAGAUUGGAGGGGCAUCUAGCACUUAACAUAUGCCACAAUGCUUUCUGUGGCCAUUAUUUAACCUCUGGUUAAACAAGCUUAGGAGGCUGACUUACUAGUAGUAAAAGGAGUGUGCUUUGAGUCACAGAUCCUGGUUGAACUCCAGCAUGUUACAAACCUCAGCCCUGUUCUAUGAAAGGUCAUAACUACGAGGAUUAUUGUAAAACAUUAAUUUAGAAAUGUAAAGUGGUCCCCAAUCUCUGGAUCUGGUCAGGAUUUAUUGGAGCUGCCACUGAGGGGAUUAAAUAAGUGGGGUCAAAGCCCCACAGCCUAGUCAACCAAGUUGCUCCUCUUUUGUCUAUCCUGUGGUUCCCAAGCAAGACUGCAAUUGAAAAAAAGGCUGCUGUUAUUAAAGUCAGAACACCAAAUAAAGCUUUUUUUUUUUUUUUGA